GGUGUUCCCGAAAGUGGAGCCAGCGCCACGCGUCUCCAGGGUCUCCAUACCCAGCCUUCGUCCCUGCGGUGCCCAGAGGCCUUGCGCGCAUUUUGCAUUUGGGAAGACAGGUCCUGAGUGCGACCGUCACCCAGCGGAAGUGUGAGGGUUCGGCCCAGCGGCAGGGCUAGCCCUGGGCCUCCUGUUAUGGCCCUGCCCAGCCCACAGGUUCUAAUGGGGUUGCCAGCGUUGCUGAUGGGCCCGGCGCAGGUAAGUGGAGUGUGCCCCAGGCCCUCACCCGCUGGGAUUCCGGCCCUCAGGAUCCUGAAGCCCAGAUAGAGGGGAUGUUGGUGUCCUGGGACUCUUGAUCGUGUCCUGUCCUCACACGUGGGUCCUGGGCCCUGCCCUGGGAGUCACUUACCCUUACCAUCCUGAAUCCAGGCAAGGGGUUAUAUCGAGGGAUUCCCAUUUCUGGAAUCCUGUGGAAUGAGAUCUGGAAGGCUGUCCCAGGGACAGUGACCAGCAUGUGUACCUUGUUUAGUGGUGAUGAAAUGGAAGCAUUCUGGGGACUGCCGGUCUCCAUUUAGUCUGGUGGAAACAGGGAAGGGAAACCAAUAGUUAGGCCUGGAAUGGCAGCCUGAGGAGCUGGACCUCUAUUCUGAUGGUGGUGGGAGCCAUGGAAGGUUUGGAGUAGAGGAAGUAGGUGCUCUGACUCCAGUCUUAACAGACGCCCUAUGGAUGCCUAGUGGGCAGCAGACUGGAGGGAUGGUGAUGGUGGAGCAGGAAGGCCAGUGAGGAGCUGACAGAUGUGGUCCAGAUGUGUGCUUUGGGUAGCUGGACAGAGGGGUGCCCGUGGAGGUAGGACAGAUGGUUGGCUUCUGAAUCUGCCCAAACUGGGCCAUGGAUUACCUGAUGUGGGACAGUGAAAGAAAGUGAAAUGUUAAGAUUGACCUAAGGCUGAGUGCAGUGGCUCACACUUGUAAUCCCAGCACUUUGGGAGGCCAAGGCGGCCAGAUCACUUGAGGUCAGGAGUUCAAGACCAGCCUGGCCAACGUGGCGAAACCCCACCUCUACUAAAAAUACAGAAAAAUUAGCCAGGACAUGGUAGUGUGCACCUGUAAUCCCAGCAACUUGGGAAACUGAGGCAGAAGAACUGUUUGAAUCUGGGAGAUGGAGGUUGCAUUGAGCUGAGAUCGUGCCACUGCGCUCCAGCCUGAGUGACAGAGCGAGACUCUGUCUUAAAAAAAAAAAAAAAUUGCCGGGCGUGGUGGCUCACGCCUGUAAUCCCAGCACUUUGGGAGGCCGAGGCAGGUGGAUCACUAGGUCAGGAGAUUGAGACCAUCCUGGCUAACACGGUGAAACCCCAUCUCUACUAAAAAUACAAAAAAUUAGUCAGGCGUGGUGGUGGGUGCCUGUAGUCCCAGCUACUCGGGAGGCUGAGGCAGGAGAAUGGCUUGAACCCGGGAGGCGGAGCUUGCAGUGAGCCAAGAUCGCGCCACUGCACUCCAACCUGGGUGACAGAGCGAGACUCUGUCUCAAAAAAAAAAAAAAAAAAAUUGACCUUAGAUCUUUCAGAUGUGGAAGUUGGUGUGAGGAGUAGAUUUCAGGGGGAAGAUAAAGAGUUGGAUUUUGGCCAUGUUGUAUUUGAGAUGUCCCAGACACUACCAAAUUGAGGUGCCAAGUAGACCACUAAACAUGUGAUUAUGAAAUUAUGUCGGGUUUAGGCUGGAAACAUCCAAGGGAUGGAUGCUUGUGUGUGGACACUGCAUGCAGUUGUGGGUUGGGUUCAAGAUAGUGGCUGAGCCUCCUGAGCAGAGAGUAGGUCUAGGACAACAGUGAAGCAUAGCGGCAAAAGUAGGAUGAGAGUUGGGCUUUGGUUUAGGUUGAUUUGCUUCUCUACAGCUCACUACAUUGUUGCGGCCAUCCUUCUUGUGGUCAGGGCAUGUUAUCUCUUCUUAAAUAGGGUCCUGGGGUUUUUGUCAGGCUGGUGGAGUGGCAAGAUCAGAAAGGGUCAGCCUAAGCUGAGUCCCCAAGCCAAGGUGGGGGCCAGUGGAUCUUGGAUUUGAGUGUUAGGAAGAGCAAGGACAGCUAUGACUGGGGAGGAGACAACACAUACAAAGGCAAAGAUAUCAGAGGGAAGAGAUAUUUGAGAUCUGCUUAUGGUUCUGGGCAGCUGAUGGUUGAAGGAACAGGGCUGGCAGGGGAGGCAUUGACUUGAGGGGCUAUGACUGCCUCUUGCAGUGGGGUUUUUGGAGCUCUGUAGCUGGCUUGGACCAGGAAUGGAUCCCGGUUGCAUCUGUCAGCAUACUUCUUGGCCCUGUGGCUCAGCUGUCCCCACAUUGAAGAGCAUGGUAACCUUUGAAGAUGUGGCUGUAUACUUCUCCCAAGAGGAGUGGGAGCUCCUUGAUGCAGCCCAGAGGCACCUGUACCACAGUGUGAUGCUGGAAAACCUUGAGCUUGUGACCUCACUUGGUUCUUGGCAUGGAGUAGAGGGUGAGGGGGCCCAUCCCAAGCAGAAUGUUUCUGUAGAAGUGUUACAGGUCAGGAUCCCUAAUGCAGAUCCUUCCACCAAGAAAGCUAACUCCUGUGACAUGUGUGGGCCAUUCUUGAAAGACAUUUUGCACCUGGCUGAGCAUCAGGGAACACAGUCUGAGGAGAAACCCUACACAUGUGGAGCAUGUGGGAGAGACUUUUGGUUGAAUGCAAACCUUCACCAGCACCAGAAGGAGCACAGUGGAGGGAAGCCCUUUAGAUGGUACAAGGACAGGGACGCACUUAUGAAGAGCUCUAAAGUCCACCUGUCAGAGAACCCCUUCACUUGCAGGGAAGGUGGGAAGGUCAUCCUGGGCAGCUGUGACCUCCUCCAGCUUCAAGCUGUUGACAGUGGGCAGAAGCCAUAUUCCAAUCUUGGGCAGCUUCCAGAAGUCUGUACCACACAGAAACUCUUCGAGUGCAGCAACUGUGGAAAAGCCUUCCUGAAGAGCUCCACUCUCCCCAACCAUCUGAGAACUCACUCUGAAGAGAUACCAUUUACAUGCCCAACAGGUGGAAAUUUCUUAGAGGAGAAAUCAAUCCUUGGUAAUAAAAAGUUUCACACUGGGGAAAUACCCCAUGUGUGUAAGGAGUGUGGGAAGGCCUUUAGUCACUCAUCUAAGCUGAGGAAGCACCAGAAAUUUCACACUGAAGUAAAAUAUUAUGAGUGCAUUGCAUGUGGGAAAACCUUCAACCACAAACUCACAUUUGUUCAUCAUCAGAGAAUUCACUCAGGAGAAAGACCUUAUGAGUGUGAUGAAUGUGGGAAAGCCUUCAGUAACAGAUCACACCUCAUUCGGCAUGAGAAAGUUCACACUGGAGAAAGGCCUUUUGAGUGCCUGAAAUGUGGAAGAGCCUUCAGCCAAAGCUCCAAUUUCCUUCGGCAUCAGAAAGUUCACACACAGGUAAGACCUUAUGAGUGCAGUCAAUGUGGUAAAUCCUUCAGCCGAAGCUCUGCUCUCAUUCAGCACUGGAGAGUUCACACUGGAGAAAGACCGUAUGAAUGCAGUGAAUGUGGAAGAGCUUUUAACAAUAACUCCAACCUUGCUCAGCACCAGAAAGUUCACACCGGAGAACGGCCUUUUGAGUGCAGUGAAUGUGGAAGAGACUUCAGCCAAAGCUCCCAUCUCCUUCGACAUCAGAAAGUUCACACUGGAGAACGGCCUUUUGAAUGCUGUGAUUGUGGUAAAGCCUUCAGUAAUAGCUCCACCCUCAUCCAGCACCAGAAAGUACAUACUGGGCAAAGGCCUUAUGAGUGCAGCGAAUGUAGGAAAUCCUUCAGCCGCAGCUCCAGCCUGAUUCAGCACUGGAGAAUUCACACUGGAGAAAAGCCUUACGAGUGUAGUGAGUGUGGGAAAGCCUUUGCUCACAGCUCCACUCUCAUUGAACACUGGAGAGUUCACACAAAAGAAAGGCCUUAUGAGUGCAAUGAAUGUGGGAAAUUCUUUAGCCAAAACUCCAUUCUCAUUAAGCAUCAGAAAGUUCAUACUGGAGAAAAGCCUUAUAAAUGCAGUGAAUGUGGGAAAUUCUUUAGCCGAAAAUCCAGCCUUAUUUGUCACUGGAGAGUUCACACUGGAGAAAGGCCUUACGAAUGCAGUGAAUGUGGGAGAGCCUUUAGCAGUAACUCCCACCUGGUUCGUCAUCAGAGAGUUCACACACAAGAAAGGCCCUAUGAGUGCAUCCAGUGUGGAAAAGCCUUUAGUGAAAGAUCUACACUUGUUCGGCACCAGAAAGUUCACACCAGAGAAAGGACUUAUGAGUGUAGCCAGUGUGGGAAACUCUUCAGCCAUCUUUGUAACCUUGCACAGCAUAAAAAGAUUCAUACCUGAGUGGAGCCUUAUGGAAGUGGUCUUUGUGAGAAAAUCUUCAGCCAAGUCAAACUUCAUGCAGCAGAAUCCCCAUACCAGAAAAAUUACCUACAUGUACUGCUAAUGUGGAAAAGCCUUCAGAAGCUACUCUGUUUCUGACCAGCCCAGGAACCUUUGCAGGGCCAUCUCACCCAUGCAGCAUAAGGCAGAAGCCAUAGUCACUUUCCAUCUUGCCUGGAUCCAAAAAUUUGCAGCAGUCCUGUCCUCAUGCAUGGGGAAAACAGUACCCUGAGCCUUCCUUCCUGUGUUCUCUAGGGAUUCAGGACUGUGCUCAGCUGAACCGAUGCUGGUUGAGGGGCCUUGAGGGAAAUCUAAUUUGAGCUCAGGAAGAUGCACAUUCCUUGUGGAUGUGGUCAAGUCUGUGUUUAACCCCUAAGAUGUGUCCAUUGAGGCCACAAAUCACCCUCCACUGGAAUCACCUACCUUGCCUGCACUAACUGGUGAUAAUAAAGACCUUAUUGAUCAGGUCA